AGUUCCACUCCCGCCUGCCAGCCCUCAACUCCCGGUCGGGUUGUCUCCCCGCCGGUCUCCCGCCCCCAGCUACCGGGUCCGCCAGGGUCAGGAGCCCGAGAUUCGCCGCCCGUCGUAGCGGCCCGCUUCGGCCCCUCGGGGCCCGGGGCUCUCCGGGACCUACACAGCCCGGGAGACUCCGGCGGGGCUGCCUGCCCUCGCCCGAGCCCGGGGGCCCAAGCUGCGGCAGCGGCUCCCAACGCCUCUGCUCGAGGAGAGCGGCGGCCUGGAUGCCCCAGCGCCCUCCCUGUCCAGUUCCUUGAAGGCCCCCAAGAGGGGCGAGGCCGGGGAGGUGCUGGAGCGGGGCCAAGUGAGCUUUCGGGGCCGCGGUUGAACUGGAGUCUUGAGUGCGCUGCGGUCAGUGGAGGCCCUUCCACCCUCGCCGCGCCCCGUGGGGAAUAGUCCCCCACCUCCCGCCAUGGCUGCAGCAGGAGGAGACGACGUCCUCCAUUUUGUCGGGACAACUGUGGGAACUUGGGACCCCUCAAAACCAAACCCCGUGGGGCCAGGACUUGUCCCGGAAGCCCCGACUGGGCUCUGCCAUUCGGACAAGGGAACAGCCCCAGCUGCCGGCGUCUGCGUCCGCGGGGCAGUACUGGUCGGGCGCGACGGUGGAGACACCCAGACGCAGCUCCCCGCCUCCAUCAACCAAGAUGGAGGGAGCUGCAGGCUCCCUUGGAGCUGGGCUCUCGCGGGUUGGAGGGGCUGAGGCCUGCCCUGGGGCGUCCCUGGGCGCCGCCGUCCUGUGCUAGCAGCCCGGGGCGCUGGCCCUGCCUAGGCCUUUUUACUGCCUGCCACCGUCUCCUGGUCCGGAAUGGUUGAUGGAGACUCCAUGGAGGCUCCCUCCACAGCCCGCUCUAUCGCGGGGCGCACCCGCUGCGGCCCCUGCGGGGAGCAGAAUCAGGGACAGAUGGCGCCCGGUGAGGGCGGGCCCCACAGGCCACCUCCACGAGGGGUCUUCUCUUUUGUUCCUCGUCUACACCUACGUCUUCGGCGGAUGUCAUGGUGCUGAACCAUUUCCCGGACUCCACGUAAAGAUGGAAGCGAUUCCGCUUUCGUCUCGCCCUGGCGGUUCUUAGUGGGAUUACAAUUGAGGAUGUUAGUUUGGAUGAAAGUUGGUGAAAUACUUACCUUAUGUCUGGAAAUACAGAUAAUGUGAUUUUUAAAAAACACAUUGAGCCCCGUUUUACUUCUGUGGUAUGGUAAAGGCACAGGUUUAUUCAAUGAAAAUCAGACGUUAACCAUCUAAUGCAGGGGUGGCCAAUCUUUUGGCUUCCCGGGGCCACAUUGGAAGAAUUGGCUUGGGCCACACAUAAAAUACGCUAACAGUAACAAUAGCUGAUGAGCUAAAACAAACGAAAAAACCAAAACGCCAAAAAAAUCUCAUAACGUUUUAAGAAAAUUUACAAAUAUGUGUUGGGCUGCAUUCAAAGCCGUCCUGGGCCGCAUGCAACCCCCAAGGGCUGCAGGUUGGACAAGCUUGAUCUAAGACAAAAGCAUGUUCACGGAUUGAUGAGAGUUCUGUGUAAGCCUUUGCAUAUUGCAUAGUGCUGUAUGUCAUGGAUAUGCCUAAUAUCACCUACAUUUUUUAGGUCCUCAGUUACUCUUUGGAAAUAAGUGAAUUACAUGUAAUGUCAUCAUUUUAAUGACUGCUGUAAAUUACAAGCACUGACUACCCUGAGUUCGUGGAGAAGGGCUCCAUAGAGAAAAUUUGAAGGUCUGACAGAAACUUUAAAUGUGAGUACCUCUAAAGCAAGCUUGUCCAACCAGUGGCCAGGAGGUGGCAUGUAGCCCAGAAUGGCUUUGAAUGCAUGUGGUCCAACACAAAUUUUGUAAACUUUCUUAAAACCCUUUCAGACAUGUGAUGCUUUCCUUGAUGUUAUGACAUAGCAAGAAGGCCCAUGACAGAUGCCAGCACCUUGAUAUUGGACUUCCCUGCCUCCAGAAUGGCAAUGGUGUCAGAUAAUCGUGAAAUUGAGAAGUCGCCCAUCCAUUUGGGUGGGAAAAUAACCAACAUCCUCAGUUGUAAUCCCACUAAGAACCGCCAGGGCGAGACGAAAGCGACAUCGCUUCCAUCUUUACGUGAGUCUUGGAAAUGGUUCAGCACCAUGACGUCCGCCGAAGACGACCAAGAAUCGCCUUCAGCCCUGUCUGGUGCAUCCUUGGCAGAAAGUGAGGAGGAAAACACCCCCAUUCCAUACAUGUGUAUAUUACUCUCUGCCGUAGUCACCUGGAUACCAUCUCUGGACUUACUAGUGUUCUUUGGCAUGGACACAAGUUCAGUGGGAGGAUUAGAAUUGACUGAUCAGACUCCUGUUUUAUUAGGGAGUACGGCCAUGGCAACUAGUCUCACGAAUGUAGGAAACUCAUUUAGUGGUCCAGCUAAUCCUUUAGUGUCUAGAUCUAAUAAGUUUCAGAACUCGUCAGUGGAAGAUGAUGAUGAUGUUGUUUUUAUCGAACCUGUACAACCUCCCCCACCUUCUGUACCAGUGGUAGCUGAUCAAAGAACCAUAACAUUUACAUCAUCAAAAAAUGAAGAACUACAAGGAAAUGAUUCCAAAAUUACUCCUUCCUCAAAAGAGUUGGCAUCUCAGAAGGGAAGUGUAAGUGAGACAAUUGUCAUUGAUGAUGAAGAGGACAUGGAAACAAAUCAAGGGCAAGAGAAAAAUUCCUCCAAUUUUAUUGAACGAAGACCUCCUGAGACUAAAAACAGAACCAAUGAUGUGGAUUUCUCCACUUCCAGUUUUUCAAGAAGUAAGGUAAAUGCAGGAAUGGGUAAUAGUGGUAUCACCACAGAACCAGACUCUGAAAUUCAGAUUGCUAAUGUUACAACUUUAGAAACAGGUGUAAGCUCUGUGAAUGAUGGCCAAUUAGAAAAUACUGACGGGCGAGAUAUGAACUUAAUGAUUACACAUGUAACAUCACUGCAGAAUACCAACUUGGGAGAUGUCUCUAACGGACUGCAGUCAAGUAAUUUUGGUGUUAAUAUACAAACAUACACCCCAUCUUUAACUUCACAGACCAAGACUGGAGUAGGACCUUUUAAUCCUGGUAGAAUGAAUGUGGCAGGAGACGUUUUUCAGAAUGGAGAAUCUGCAACUCAUCAUAAUCCUGAUUCUUGGAUCUCCCAGUCAGCUUCAUUUCCCCGUAAUCAGAAACAACCAGGGGUGGACUCUUUAUCACCAGUGGCCUCACUUCCUAAACAGAUUUUCCAGCCGUCUGUCCAACAGCAGCCUACUAAACCAGUUAAAGUCACUUGUGCAAACUGCAAAAAACCUUUACAGAAGGGCCAGACAGCUUAUCAACGAAAAGGAUCAGCUCACCUCUUUUGUUCUACCACCUGCCUUUCUUCCUUCUCCCACAAGCCUGCUCCAAAGAAACUCUGUGUUAUGUGUAAAAAAGAUAUAACUACAAUGAAAGGAACCAUUGUUGCUCAAGUGGAUUCAAGUGAGUCCUUCCAGGAAUUCUGUAGUACAUCUUGUUUAUCUCUCUAUGAAGACAAACAGAAUCCUACUAAAGGAGCUCUAAAUAAAUCAAGAUGUACAAUCUGUGGUAAACUAACUGAGAUUCGCCAUGAAGUCAGCUUUAAAAAUAUGACUCAUAAGCUGUGCAGUGACCACUGCUUUAAUAGAUAUAGAAUGGCCAAUGGUUUAAUAAUGAAUUGCUGUGAACAGUGUGGAGAGUACUUGCCCAGUAAAGGUGCUGGAAAUAAUGUUCUGGUGAUUGAUGGUCAACAGAAAAGAUUUUGCUGUCAAAGUUGUGUCAGUGAAUACAAACAGGUAGGUAGCCAUCCAAGCUUCCUGAAGGAGGUUCGAGAUCACAUGCAGGACUCUUUCUUAAUGCAGCCUGAGAAAUAUGGAAAACUGACAACUUGUACUGGUUGCCGAACACAGUGCAGGUUUUUUGAUAUGACUCAGUGUAUAGGUCCUAAUGGAUAUAUGGAGCCAUAUUGUUCAACUGCUUGUAUGAACAGUCACAAGACAAAAUAUGCAAAAUCACAAAGUUUGGGAAUUAUUUGCCAUUUUUGUAAGCGAAACUCUUUACCUCAAUACCAAGCCACAAUGCCUGAUGGAAAACUGUACAACUUUUGCAAUUCCAGUUGUGUGGCUAAAUUUCAGGCUCUAAGUAUGCAGUCAUCUCCAAAUGGCCAGUUUGUAGCGCCAAGUGAUAUUCAGUUGAAAUGCAACUACUGCAAAAAUUCCUUUUGUUCAAAACCAGAAAUCCUGGAAUGGGAGAACAAAGUGCAUCAGUUCUGCAGCAAAACUUGUUCAGAUGACUAUAAGAAGUUGCAUUGCAUAGUUACAUAUUGCGAAUACUGUCAAGAGGAGAAGACUCUUCAUGAAACAGUAAAUUUCUCUGGCGUUAAGAGACCUUUCUGUAGUGAAGGCUGCAAAUUAUUAUACAAACAGGAUUUUGCCAGACGUUUAGGAUUGAGAUGUGUUACUUGCAACUAUUGUUCUCAGCUAUGUAAGAAGGGAGCAACUAAAGAACUCGAUGGUGUUGUGAGAGAUUUCUGCAGUGAAGAUUGCUGUAAAAAAUUUCAGGAUUGGUACUACAAGGCUGCAAGGUGUGACUGUUGUAAAUCUCAAGGAACUCUUAAAGAGCGAGUUCAGUGGCGUGGGGAAAUGAAACAUUUCUGUGAUCAACAUUGCUUACUGCGUUUCUACUGUCAACAAAAUGAGCCCAACAUGACAACUCAGAAAGGACCUGAAAACUUACAUUAUGAUCAGGGUUGUCAGACAUCUCGAACCAAAAUGACAGGUUCAGCACCACCCCCUUCUCCAACACCUAACAAAGAGAUGAAGAACAAAGCAGUUCUUUGCAAACCUUUAACAAUGACAAAAGCUACUUACUGUAAACCUCACAUGCAGACCAAAUCUUGUCAGACAGAUGAUACUUGGAGGACAGAAUAUGUUCCAGUGCCUAUCCCUGUGCCUGUGUAUAUCCCAGUUCCUAUGCACAUGUACAGUCAGAAUAUUCCUGUUCCUACUACAGUUCCUGUUCCUGUGCCAGUUCCUGUUUUUCUGCCUGCUCCAUUGGACAGCAGUGAGAAGAUUCCUGCAGCAAUUGAGGAGCUAAAAAGCAAGGUUUCUUCAGAUGCUCUUGAUACAGAGUUGCUUACAAUGACGGAUAUGAUGAGUGAAGACGAGGGGAAAACAGAGACAACCAACAUCAACAGUGUAAUUAUUGAAACAGAUAUAAUUGGUUCAGACCUUUUGAAGAACUCUGACCCAGAGACACAGUCCAGCAUGCCUGAUGUACCAUAUGAACCAGAUUUGGAUAUCGAAAUAGAUUUUCCCAGAGCUGCUGAGGAGCUUGAUAUGGAAAAUGAAUUUUUAUUACCACCUGUUUUUGGCGAAGAAUAUGAGGAACAGCCCAGACCUCGAUCUAAAAAAAAGGGAGCCAAGAGAAAGGCUGUAUCAGGAUACCAGUCUCAUGAUGAUAGUUCUGACAAUUCAGAAUGCAGCUUUCCUUUCAAAUAUACGUAUGGCGUAAAUGCAUGGAAACACUGGGUCAAAACUAGGCAACUUGAUGAAGAUCUUCUGGUAUUAGAUGAGUUAAAAUCUUCUAAAUCAGUAAAGUUAAAAGAGGAUCUACUCUCUCACACCACAGCUGAGCUUAACUAUGGGUUAGCUCAUUUUGUCAAUGAGAUCCGACGGCCAAAUGGAGAGAAUUAUGCACCUGACAGCAUCUAUUACCUUUGCCUUGGAAUACAGGAGUAUUUGUGUGGAAGUAAUCGAAAAGACAACAUAUUUAUUGAUCCUGGAUACCAAACAUUUGAGCAAGAAUUGAAUAAAAUACUGCGAAGCUGGCAACCAAGCAUACUUCCAGAUGGGUCAAUAUUCUCUCGAGUUGAAGAAGACUAUCUCUGGAGGAUAAAACAACUAGGAUCACACUCUCCAGUAGCUCUUCUGAAUACACUGUUCUACUUUAACACUAAGUAUUUUGGCCUGAAAACAGUGGAACAACACUUAAGACUUUCCUUUGGCACUGUGUUUAGGCAUUGGAAAAAAAAUCCUUUAACGAUGGAAAACAAAGCGUGUCUUCGAUACCAAGUGUCUUCCUUGUGUGGAACAGAUAAUGAAGAUAAAAUUACUACUGGAAAAAGAAAACAUGAAGAUGAUGAGCCAGUAUUUGAACAAAUUGAAAACACAGCCAAUCCUUCCAGAUGUCCUGUGAAAAUGUUUGAAUGCUACUUGUCUAAAAGUCCACAGAAUCUUAAUCAGAGGAUGGAUGUUUUUUAUUUGCAACCAGAAUGCUCUAGUUCUACAGAUAGCCCUGUCUGGUAUACGUCUACUUCACUGGACCGAAACACCUUGGAAAAUAUGCUUGUACGGGUUCUUCUAGUAAAAGAUAUUUAUGAUAAAGACAAUUAUGAACUGGAUGAAGACACAGACUAAAAAGGAACGUUGCAGAAGCAAUCGGGAUAAAACAGCAUUAGAUAGUCAUGCUGCUAGAUCUUUAUUAUGGAAAACAUUUCAAGUUUACUCCUUCUGUUUUGAGUUUUGUAGCAGUGUACCCACGCUGGGUAUUACCAUGUAAAUAAUCUGUGAGUGAAAGUUGCCAUUAUUCUAUGUAGUGGUUUUAGGAUACUUAACAAAUACAUUCAAAUUCUUUUUUUAUUAUUAUUUAUUUGAUUAGGUAUGUUUGUAACUUUUUACAUUACAGAAUAUGAAUGAGAAUGUGCCAUGUAUAAUUUUUUUCUUGUAGUAAGAAACAUCCAUAUUGCACAACUCUACUGUUGCAAAGCUUCCUUGGAAGGGGGCUCUUUUACUGGGUUCUUAACCAGAUGGUUGUGUAUGGGUAGCACUACUAAAAGUUUAGAACUUGCAGUGUCUUUCGGAAUUUUUAAAAUAAACUGUAAACUAAUAGGCUGGGGUUUUUGUUUUGUUUUGGGGUUUUGUUUUGUUUGGUUUUACAUUUUAGUUACUGAAGCCUUACAAGGUUAUGUAGAGAGAUACCAUCUUCUGUACCAAAAAUAGACAAGAGAAUGCUGUCAAUAUUGGUGUACUGUAAUGUGAAUCUAUGCUGGUGAAAACAAUUUUUUGUUCCCCUUAUUAAAACCUUAGUGUCCUUUUCUCAUUUGUGGCUUUCUGCAUCACCCAAUCAAUAAAAAACAAAUAUAUAUAUGUAUAUAUAUGUAUGUAUGUGUGUGUGUAUAUAUAUAUAUAUAUAUAUAUAUAUAAAUGAUUGUAAGUUGAAAACAAGAUCAUCAAGACAUUUCCUUUGUAAAAAUGUCUGGUGAAAGUAUAAAAUUCUGUUUUCUUCUAUGCCAGCCAUAAGUAUCUGAAAUCCUCUUCAUUUAUAGAGGUUUGAUUUUUAUUUCUUUUUUUCCCUCUUAAGGAUACAGAUCAUGCUGCAAUGUUAGCUGUGUAGUACUCUAAAACUUAGCAAUUUUAUCAGAAUUCUUGUGCCUGUUUACAUUGGAUAAAAUUGUUUUUAGAAAUUCCACUCCUGAAAUAGUUACAGAAAGUCAAGCUAUGUUAAAUAAGAUAGGAUCACAUUUUAUAAUGAAGAUUACCAGUGUAGUAAUUCUGAUAUUGCAAAUGAUUGAGGAACAAACAAAGAAACUAAUAGAGAAAGUCAGUCUCAGAGGAAAUCCCAUUUAAUGUUAGAUUGUUUGGCUUUUGAAAUUACUUCUUAUAGAAGAUUGCAUUAAAAAAAAAAACAACUUUGUGCUUCUGCAUAGCAAUUUAUCCAUUCAGACCUUUUCUUUUAGAAUAAGGAAACUUAAAAUCUACUUUCUAAAGACUGAACAAAGUGCUAGCUGCAAAUUAUCUUGAAAUCAUUUGGCUCUUUUCUAGCAUGUGUGUAAUCAUGUUUUCUUCUGAUUCCUGAAUGACCAUGGUAGCAUUAGUGUUUAGAAAUUGUUCAGGGGAAAAUUGAGCUAUUUUCCAUAGUGGCUAGCAAUUGCUACACAUCCUUAGAUACUCCUCUCUCCCAUAGGAUAAAUGUUACAGCACACAAAAGAAAUUUUCUCAAUUCUGAUUUGGAAAAUUUCACAGGUGUCAUUAUUGUAUAUCUAAGCAAUAAUUAUCUGAAUGUUUUGGCAUAAAAAAUUAUAAUGUUCUAACUUGUUUUAUAAGUUGAAUGACUUUUCAGUCCCUUGAUUUUAUAUUGUUGAGUGAUAAUCAGACUGAUAGUAGCAAAUCUGAUCAUACAUUACUAAAAUAGAUUGCUGAUUGUCUAUUUAACGAAGACAAGUGGGUAACAUUUAAAAUAUAUAAUACAAAAAUUUUCUCUAACUUACCUUUUUCCAGAACUACUUCUUUAAGCACUUUUCCUAUUAAUGCCUAUUGUUGAUUAAAAGGUGGUUAAUUCUAACCAUCUUUUAGUCUUCAAAGUGGUGCUAUAUUCCAUCAAGAGCAAUAAAGUUUUUCCCAGGUGUCACUUAUUGUAUAUGUUACCAAAUACCAUGAAUUUCUGCCAUAGUACUACUAUCAAGCACCUUGUCUUGCUAUUUACAGUUUCUUCAUUUGUAUAUUUUUAGCUUUUCUAAGUGGAAAUGUCUACAUAAUUUUGAUCUUGACAUGAUUGAGGAUUUAGAGCUCUUGUCUUUGUCUUGAUUGCAAUCCAACGAUAGAUUAACUUGAUUCUCAGGGGGAAAAGAAAAACUUAUUUUAUGAGAAUUGUUUGUUCUGUGAAACUCACUUCACCUAGAACACAUUUCAUUGAUUCUUGGAUCUUAGUUUAUGUGGUCAUAGUUGACUGCUGAGAAAAGGACAAUGAAAUGAUAGCAAUUUCCUUUUGCUUCUAGGUGAUCUCUGAUUAUAGAUAGCAUCCUGUAAAUAUAACUUUAUUGUCUUGAAAUGUUUAUUGAAGAUGCUAUAUUUUUCUGUUCUGUUUUCUGAAGAUUUUGCCAUUUAAAAUGAUCCAGUGAAAAAUAUUUAUCCACAUUGAAGAAAGUGGAUUUCCCAUGCAAAUUGAAUCUUCAUUAACACAUUUUAAAAGGCUUUACUGUAUUAGGUAACAUAGAUAUUAAAGGAUUUUUCUAGGCAAGAAGCUCAACUUUUUUUUUCCAUAAAAAUAAUUUUUGCUUAAAUAGUAACUCAUGGUUUUCUUUUAUUAAAUGGGGUUGUUGUCAGUAUGUUAAACAUUGAAGUAGGAGGAGGAUGCAUAUUGUACUAUGCAUUCAAAUUUAUCACUGUUUUUUCUGACAGACUUUCCCUUUGUCCUUUCUAGUUAUGACUUGGGAAUGGGGUAACUUCUUUAUGCAUAGUAUUAAGGGUUAUAGUAUGAAGAAAUCAUAAAAUUGCAAGUUUUGGUUUGCAUUACUCUAAUGUGGGUUCAUUUAAUCUGAGAUCUUAAAUAUCUUGCAGCCUUAAAUCACUACAAACAUUUGCAUUUUUAUUAUGCCAGUUAUUUCCAAAAUGUAUUGUUAUACAUGUCACUUAUGUUUUUAAGCUAAUAUUGACUGUAGGAUAAUCUCCUUGUUCCCCUCAAAAUAGUCAUGAAAGUGUACAUGAAAAUAUUUUUAAAGAAUAAAUUUCUUUAAAUUACA